CUUUUUCCACAAUGAGCAGCAACUAUUGUUUGGUACAAAGUAAAAAGCAGUGUAGGUUGCCCCACGCAGGUGUGCCUAGGUGUGUGCUCCUCCAGUGCUGAGAACCCUGCUGUACCUGGCUUUGGACCAGGUCCUUCACCUUUUUGGGCUCACUCUCCUCAUUUGUAAAAUGGGACUUUUCAUAUGGCCUGCCCACCUGUAGGGAGGCAGGUGCGAUGCUAGGUAUAAAGGGGGACUGUUGAGUACCAUAACAUACAGGCAGUGGUUACUGUUCUUGAUUUGCUUGUGUGUUUUGUUUUUUGAAUUUUUUUUCCCAGAAGCAGGUUUCUCCUCUUGACAGCCUCUCCUAGCUCUUUGACUUUGGGGAUGGGGGACUGGGAGUAGUCAGAAUUUUUUGCUCCCUACAUGAAAAGGCUUUGAGCUGGAGACAGGAGGCACUUGCCCCCUGGACAGAUUCACAGGAAGAGAACUGCAGGUAAUUUACAAAUGGAAUUUCUCUAUAUGCAUCCAGAGGUCUAGGGGUGCAGAAAGAUUGAGGUCCACUCCCAGAGCGCCCCUUUUACAUGUGUACAUUCUCUCUCUCUCACACACACAUGCACACACACACACACGUGUGUUUUUAAACACAUUUGGUAACAUGCCCUUUUGAAAUCUAAAGUUUCACCUACUGCAUCUUGAACAUUUGCCAUGCCCUUCAGCUCCCAUGGGAUCAUGCCUUUGAGCAGCCGCACAGCAGUAUGUCAUUUGGAUAUAUUGUUGUUGGCUGGGCAAGCCCCACUUGGAAGGGAUUUGUGAUCACUGAAGCCUCUCUUUAAGGUCUGUGGCCCCCGCUGCCUGCUUCACUGGCUCAGCCUCUGGAAGAGGAGACAGUGCUUCUGCAAAUCCUCCUAGCAGCCUCCUAGAGAGCCUGCCUUUUAUCCGAUGAGGAAGCAGGCCCGGGGCAGAUGUGUGACGGGAGCCACUUGGCCUCCACCCUCCGCUAUUGCAUGACAGUCAGCGGCACAGUGGUUCUGGUGGCCGGGACGCUCUGCUUCGCUUGGUGGAGCGAAGGGGAUGCAACCGCCCAGCCUGGCCAGCUGGCCCCACCCACGGAGUAUCCGGUGCCUGAGGGCCCCAGCCCCCUGCUCAGGUCCGUCAGCUUCGUCUGCUGCGGUGCAGGUGGCCUGCUGCUGCUCAUUGGCCUGCUGUGGUCCGUCAAGGCCAGCAUCCCAGGGCCACCUCGAUGGGACCCCUAUCACCUCUCCAGAGACCUGUACUACCUCACUGUGGAGUCCUCAGAGAAGGAGAGCUGCAGGACCCCCAAAGUGGUUGACAUCCCCACUUACGAGGAAGCCGUGAGCUUCCCAGUGGCCGAGGGGCCCCCAACACCACCUGCAUACCCUACGGAGGAAGCCCUGGAGCCAAGUGGAUCGAGGGAUGCCCUGCUCAGCACCCAGCCCGCCUGGCCUCCACCCAGCUAUGAGAGCAUCAGCCUUGCUCUUGAUGCCGUUUCUGCGGAGACGACACCGAGUGCCACACGCUCCUGCUCAGGCCUGGUUCAGACUGCACGGGGAGGAAGUUAAAGGCUCCUAGCAGGUCCUGAAUCCAGAGACAAAAAUGCCGUGCCUUCUCCAGAGUCUUAUGCAGUGCCUGGGACACAGUAGGCACUCAGCAAACGUUCGUUGUUGAAGGCUGUUCUAUUUAUCUAUUGCUGUAUAACAAACCACCCCAGAAUUUAGUGGCUUAAAAUAAAUCCCAUUUUAUUAUG